CAGGUUUCAUGGCCCCCGAGCUCCUGCAGGGCGAGGAGUACGACUUCUCCGUGGACUACUUUGCCCUGGGGGUCACCCUGUAUGAGAUGAUUGCGGCCAGAGGACCCUUCCGAGCCCGUGGAGAGAAGGUGGAGAACAAGGAGCUGAAGCACCGGAUCAUCUCAGAGCCCGUGAAGUACCCUGAUAAGUUCAGCCAGGCCAGCAAGGACUUCUGCGAGGCGCUGCUGGAGAAGGACCCGGAGAAGCGCCUGGGGUUCAGAGAUGAGACCUGCGACAAGCUCCGUGCCCACCCCCUCUUCAAGGACCUUAACUGGAGGCAGCUGGAGGCUGGGAUGCUGAUGCCCCCUUUCAUCCCAGACUCCAAAACUGUCUACGCAAAGGAUAUUCAGGACGUGGGUGCCUUUUCCACCGUCAAAGGUGUGGCCUUUGACAAAACAGACACAGAAUUCUUUCAGGAAUUUGCCACUGGCAACUGCCCCAUCCCCUGGCAGGAGGAGAUGAUCGAGACGGGCAUCUUUGGCGAGCUGAACGUGUGGCGCUCGGACGGUCAGAUGCCGGACGACAUGAAGGGCAUCUCCGGGGGCUCCAGCUCCUCGUCCAAGUCAGGGAUGUGUCUGGUUUCCUAGGUGACGCCCCAGAGUCCACGUGGAGGAAAAGGACCCAUACGGCUCGAUGGGGGCCGCCUGCCUCCGUGGUGCCAGCCUGGGGUCUGCUAGCAAGGGGACACGUGGUUCCCUCCACCCAGGUCCCCAUCACGCCAUCUCCUUGCGGCCCAAGGAGGAGAAAGCCCACAUCGGCCUGAGCCGCCAGACGCACAUGCUGGUGCCGUGAGCCCCCGACUGCAUAUUUCACGUCUUUUGCUCCAUCUCACUGAGAAGACAUAAGAUGCUCUCCAGAGGGAGUAAGCCAAAAAUCUACAAACUCUUAGGGAGCCUCCUGCAUUGGUGAUUGACCAACCGUGUGGUCAGGGGCAGAGACUCGGUUUUGGCCUCCCAAGACCUUAGCCAUUGGCUUCCCAGAGCCACGCUCCUCAGCGGGAGGUGCACGGUGGCCAGGUCAGGGGUCAGUGAACCCUGGCCGCAGCCCCUGGCCCCACUGGGGAGGGCUGGACCUCGCCCCCCCCAGGUCCCUCUGUGCAGGCUCCUGCCUUCCAGGGUGCCCGGGCCCUGUGCUGGUGGCCUGCACGCCACAUGGUCCCCUGCACCCUGCGGCGCCGUGGUCCUCUGCACACUGGGGCACCAUGGUCCCCUGCACUCCGGGGUGCCGUGGUCCACAUCUGCCAGGCGCAGGCUCUGUUGGGCUGUUGGGAGGAGGGGAGCGGGUGUGGAGUCUGGGGGUCUCAGUGCAUCUUGGGGUCUCCUUAUCUCAGGGUGUCCAGCUGACGGCAGCUGGUGCAAAGUUCCCACCCCUGAGCUGGGGAGCUGAAAAUGUUUUCUGUCUUGACCCUGAGUCCCGGAAGCACCUCAGCUGCUCUUGGCGGGCAAAGCCAGGACCGUUUGCUCUCUGACCCUCCUCCCCACUGGGGCUGGUCCGUCUCAUCUCCCAGGGGACACUUCAGGCCACGGGCCUUGUGCAUAGGGACAGAGCUCCUUGCUGCAACCCCUCUCUGUGUUCCCAGUAGCAGCAGCACUGGAGUCCUAAAGCCAUAGCCCGGGAAGACACUCACAGCCCACCUUCUCAUACAGCUCGGCCCCACCCACAAUGCACCUGGCAUUUCCAACUGCACUUUGAACACUGAAGGUUCCCCAAAUGCUUUGUGUGUUUUAACUGCAGGAAGUUAGUUCUGUUGCAACUGCCUCCAGGACACACUCCCUCUUGAGGGCCGGCGGUGCUGGCCUGGGUUCCAUGGCCUCAGCAGCCGGCUCAGAGGGAGUGCAUCCAAGCCGCAGGGAAGCAGUGGUGAUGGGUGGCCUGAGGACUCCUUUCCAGAGAGGGCCUCUGAGCUCCUUUUAGGAAAGAACUUCCUUUGAGCCCCGGCCACUGUUGUACCAGUGGGAGAAGAAGCCUGACCCUGCCACAUGUGGUCACGGGGAGAGAAGAUGGUAGGACGUCCCCGUGAGCCUUGGGGCAGAGCUGGUGGUAGAAAGAAGCCCUGUCUACUCUAAUUUGGUGAGAGGGGCCGCGGCAAGUGGCUGAUGAUGUGACUGAUGGAGACAGGGUGGCUUGGGAAGGUCCCACUUGGGGGUGUCACGUCCUGCAGGGAGUGGAAGAGAUGGAUCCUCCGUAGCCUGGACUGGUGGGUCUCGGCCUCUCUCCCAGAAAUGGCAGAGACAGCUGCCUGAGAGUCAGUGCUGCAGUGGGCAGGGCCUAUGCCCUCACAGUCCUCAGGCUGCCAGGUCGUCCUCUUCCUGUUGGGGAGAAGAGGACCCUGGCAAUCCACAAUUUUGGAGAUUUGCUGGCUGCAGCCAAAAUGGGGACCCAACUCCCUCCUAUGUGGUUUUAGAGCUUCUGGAGGGAAGAUAGGCCACGCCCCUGGGUGAGGAGCACGUCUUCCCACAGAUCCUAAGUCGGCCACACCCUGGGUGAGGAGCACGUCUUCCCAUAGGUCCCACAUCAGCCACACCCUGGGUGAGGAGCACGUCUUCCCAUAGAUCCCAAGUCGGCCACACCCUGGGUGAGGAGCACGUCUUCCCAUAGAUCCCACGUCGGCCACACCCCGGGUGAGGAGCACGUCUUCCCAUAGAUCCCACAUCGGCCACACCCCGGGUGAGGAGCAUGUCUUCCCAUAGAUCCCACAUCGGCCACACCCCGGGUGAGGAGCACGUCUUCCCAUAGAUCCCACGUCGGCCACACCCUGGGUGAGGAGCACGUCUUCCCAUAGAUCCCACAUCGGCCACACCCUGGGUCCCACAGAUCUCAACAGAACUCCACAUCGUCUGGUUUUGUGGAGACUUUCAUAUGUCCUGUCAAGUUGCCUCAUGCACCUGCAGACUGUUCUUGGGAAGCAAACCUGGACUGCAAAAUAAACCUCCCGGCCUCCUCCUG